AUAUGAACUCUCCCGCCACCCGGGAACAGUGGCUGCCACCGUUUGUGUUUUCCCGAGUUUGAAUUCUUGCAGGUGACCAAGAUGGAGUUUUCUGGAAGAAAGUGGAGGAAGCUGAGGUUGGCAGGUGACCAGAGGAAUGCUUCCUACCCUCAUUGCCUUCAGUUUUACUUGCAGCCACCUUCUGAAAACAUAUCUUUAAUAGAAUUUGAAAACUUGGCUAUUGAUAGAGUUAAAUUGUUAAAAUCAGUUGAAAAUCUUGGAGUGAGCUAUGUGAAAGGAACUGAACAAUACCAGAGUAAGUUGGAGAGUGAGCUUCGGAAGCUCAAGUUUUCCUACAGAGAAAACUUAGAAGAUGAAUAUGAACCACGAAGAAGAGAUCAUAUUUCUCAUUUUAUUUUGCGGCUUGCUUAUUGCCAGUCUGAAGAACUUAGACGCUGGUUCAUUCAACAAGAAAUGGAUCUCCUUCGAUUUAGAUUUAGUAUUUUACCCAAGGAUAAAAUUCAGGAUUUCUUAAAGGAUAGCCAAUUGCAGUUUGAGGCUAUAAGUGAUGAAGAGAAGACUCUUCGAGAACAGGAGAUUGUUGCCUCAUCACCAAGUUUAAGUGGACUUAAGUUGGGGUUCGAGUCCAUUUAUAAGAUCCCUUUUGCUGAUGCUCUGGAUUUGUUUCGAGGAAGGAAAGUCUAUUUGGAAGAUGGCUUUGCUUACGUACCACUUAAGGACAUUGUGGCAAUCAUCCUGAAUGAAUUUAGAGCCAAACUGUCCAAGGCUUUGGCAGCUGGAGUGCAGUGGCGUGAUCUCGGCUCACUGCAGCCUCUGCCUCCCGGGUUCAAGCGAUUCUCCUACCUCAGCCUUCUGAGUUGCUGGGACUACAGAUGCACACCACCACACCCAGGUAAUUUUUGUAUUUUUAGUAGAGGUGGGGUUUCACCGUGUUGGCCAGGAUGGUCUCGAUCUCUUGACCUCAUGAUCUGCUUGCCUCGGCCUCCCAGAAUGGUGGGAUUACAGACAUGAGCCACCACGCCUGGCCAAUCUUUCUAACUUUUUAUGUGGCUAUUUAGUGCUAUGAAUUUCCCUCUUAACACUGCCUUAGCUGUAUCCCAGAAAUUCUAAUAUGUUGUAUCUUUGCCCUCAUUAGUUUAAAAGAACUUCUUAAUUUCUGCCUUAAUUUCAUUUUUUACCCAAAAGUCAUUCAGAAGCAUGUUAAUUUUCAUGUAAUCACAUGGUUUUGGGUGAUUUUCUUAGUCUUGACUUCUAUUAUUAUUGCAUGGUGGUCCGUGAGUGUGUUUGUUAUGAUUUAUGUUAUUUUGCAUUUGCUGAGGAUAUUUUAUGUCCAAUUAUGUGGUCGCUUUUAGAGCAUUUGCUGUGUGGUGAUGAGAAGAAUGUAUAUUUUAUUGGUUUUGGAUGGAGAGUUCUGUAGAGGUCCAUCAGAUCCAUUUGGUCCAGUGUUGAGUUCAGGUCCUAAAUAUCUUCGUUAAUUUUCUGCCUCAAUGAUUUGUCUAAUACUGUUGGUGGAAUGUUGAAGUUUCACAGUAUUAUUUUGUGGGAAUCUAUGUCUCUUUGUAGGUCUCUAAGAACUUGCUGUAUGAAUCUGGGUGCUCCUGUGUUGAGUGCAUAUAUAUUUAGGAUGGUUAGGUCUUUUAUUCAAUUGAAGUCUUUACCGUUAUGAAAUGCCCUUUUUUGUCUUUUUUUUAUCUUUUGUUUUGUUUGAAUUCUGUUUUGUCUGAAAUUGGGAUUGCAACCCCUGUUUUUUUCUGAUUUCCAUUUGCUUGGUAGAUAUUCCUGUAUCCCUUUAUUUAUUUAAUUAUUUUUUAUUUAUCUAUUUUAUUAUACUUUAGGUUCUAGGGUACAUGUGUACAACAUGCAGGUUUGUUACAUAUGUAUACAUGUGUCAUGUUGGUGUGCUGCACCCAUUAACUCAUCAUUUACAUUAGGUAUAUCUCCUAGUGCUAUCCCUCCUCCAUCCCCUGACCCCACGACAGGCCCUGGUGUGUGAUAUUCCCCACCCUGUGUCCAAGUGUUCUCACUGUUCAGUUCCCACCUAUGAGUGAGAACAUGCAGUGUUUUGUUUUCUGGCCUUGCGAUAGUUUGCUCAGAAUGAUGGUUUCUAGCUUCAUCCAUGUCCCUACGAAGGACAUGAACUCUUCCUUUUUUAUGGCUGCAAAGUAUUCCAUGGUGUACAUGUGCCACAUUUUCUUAAUCCAGUCUAUCAUUGAUGGACAUUUGGGUUGGUUCCAAGUCUUUGCUAUUGUGAAUAGUGCCGCAGUAAACACACGUGUGCAUAUGUCUUUAUAGCAGCAUGAUUUAUAAUCCUUUGGAUAUAUACCCAGUAAUGGGAUUGCUGGGUCAAAUGGUAUUUCUAGUUCUAGAUCCUUGAGGAGUCACCACACUGUCUUUCACAAUGGUUGAACUAGUUUACAGUCCCACCAACAGUGUAAAAUUGUUCUUAUUUCUCCACAUCCUCUCCAGCACCUGUUGUUUCCUGACUUUUUAAUGAUCGCCAUUCUAACUGGUGUGAGAUGGUAUCUCAUUGUGGUUUUGAUUUGUAUUUCUCUGAUGGCCAGUGAUGAUGAGCAUUUUUUCAUGUGUCUUUUGGCUGCAUAAAUGUCUUCUUUUGAGAAGUGUCUGUUCAUAUCCUUUGCCCACUUUUUGAUGGGGUUGUUUGAUUUUUUUUCUUGUAAAUUUGUUUGAGUUCAUUGUAGAUUCUGGAUAUUAGCCCUUUGUCAGAUGUGUGUUCCUUUAUUUUGAGCCUAUGGUUGUCAUUACGAGACCCAUUAAGAAAUGGGUCUCUUGAAGACAGCAUACCAUUGGGUCUUGCUUUUUUAUCCAGCUUGCCACCUGUGCCUUUGAAGUGGGACAUGUAGUCCAUUUACAUUAAAUGUUUGUAUUGAUAUGUGUACAUUUGAUCCUGUCAUUGUGUUGUUAGCUGGUUAUUCUGCUGGCUUGUUUGUGUGGUUGCUUUAUAUUGUCACUGAUCCGUGUAUUUAAGUGUCUUUUUGUAUUAGCUGGUAGCAGUCUUUCCUUUCUAUAUAUAAUGCUCCUUUCAAGAUCUCUUGUAAGGCAGGCUGGUGGUAAUUAACUUCCUCAACAUUUUCUUAUCUGAAAAGGAUCAUAUUUCUCCUUCACUUAGGAAGCUUAGUUUGGCUGGAUGUGAAAUUCUUGAUUGAAGGUUUCUUUAAUAAAUAUUGAAUAUAGGCCCCUAAUCUUUUCUGGAUUGUAAAGUUUCAGCUGAGUGAUCUGCUGUUAGCCUGAUGGGGUUCCCUUUGUAGGUGACAUGUCCUUUCUCUCUAGCUGCCUUUAACAUACUUUCUUCCAUUUUGACCUUUGAAAAUCUGUUGAUUAUGUGUCUUGGGGAUGAUCUUCUUACGUAGAAUCUUGCAAGAGUUCUCUGUAUUUCCUGAAUUUAACUGUUGGCCUCUCUCACAAGAUUAGGAAAGUUUUCAUGGAUGAUAUUCUGAAAUAUGUUUUCCAAGUUGUUUGCUUUUUCCCCUUCGCUUUCAGGGAUAAAAGUGAAUAAUCCCAUACUUCUUGGAGGUUUUGUUCAUUGCAUUGUAGGAAUGGACAAAAAAGUAGGUCUACUUUUAUUCUUUUUGCUUUAUUUUUGUCUGACUGUCUUAUUUCAGAGAGCCAGUCUUUAAGUUCUGAGAUUCUUUCUUCAGCUUGGUUUAUUCUGCUGUUAAUACUUGUGAUUGGAUUGUGAAAUUCUUGUAUUGUGUUAUUCAGCCCUGUCAGAUGCGUUACGUUCUUUUUUAUACUGGCUAUUUCCUCCUUCAGCUCCUUUAUCAUUUGGUUGUGAUUCUUAGUUUUCUUGGAUUGGGUUUGAGUCUUGAUGAUCUUUAUUCCUGUCCAUAUUUUGAACUUUAUUUCCGUCAUUUCAGCCAGCUCAGCCUGGUUGACAACUCUUGUUGGAGGGCUGAUGUGGUUGUUUGGAGAACAUGCGUCACUCUGGUCAUUUGAGUUAUUGGAGUUCUUGCUUUGGUUCUUUCUCAUCUCUGCAUAUGGCUGUUACUUUAACCUCAGUGUAGAUCGAGUAGUCAGUAGUCUAUUGAGAAGUCAAUAGACUUCUUUUCUUGUGUUUUCACAGGGCCAAGCCUUUGUGCAGGGUCUUGAUGUGAAGCUGACUUCUUGUCUUUAGUUUAAGAGGAGGGUAUAUUAGCAAGCUAUUUCUGGUGUUGAAGCUUUGGGGUGUGAUGCGGUAGGUGACAUUUAGGCAUAUUAAUCAGCUGGUAGACUCUUGCUUGGUUUUGUGGCUCCCUUAUAUUUCCUUACAGGUGGAGCCAUGUUCCCUCUUAAUGUGUGGGGUCCUCUCCCCUUUGAGUGCUGGCUGUAGAUUGCAGCUUGGCACUCCUGGGCCUGCCCAGUGCAGUUCUGGAUGUGCUCAGUGUUUAUGUUCCUUCCCCAUCUUGGAGACAGCAGAGAAAGGGACCUUAGUAGUGUUUGUGCCAAGGGUCUUUUGCUUGUCUCAUGGGGGCUCCACUCCAGAGACGUGCAGGUCUGCAAUCACCCAGUGCAAUCAGCCCAGGAUGGAGGGCCUGUGCUGUGGCCCCAGCCAGGGGUUCUCUGUCUGGUGAUGAGCACUGGGGGUGGGUAGGUGGAACCCAUGGGAGAUGGACUGGUCUCCUCCCCUUGGCUCAACUGCAGCUUGUUGGAGGUAUGGAUAAGGCAUUGAGGGUCUUUGCUCCUUCAUUAGUCUGAGGGUAGCAAGGGCAGUUCUGCUGCAGAGGCAGUGGCAGGGAGGCUUUCAGUUGCCCCUGGUUGCUCUGUCCAGGGAGUUGCAGAGCUGCUACUGGUUUGAUAUAUCUGGCAGGGGGUGGCUGGAGGCCCAGGCCUGGCGGACCUGCCCAGUGAGGAGAUAAUAUGGGAACAUGCACCUACAUAACAGGCUGGCCACUUUUCCAUAGGGCUGCUGUGGUAUCCUGGGGGCCCACUCCAGUCCCUAGUCACCUUGGAUUUUCCAGUACCUGGAGGUAUCAACAGUGAAGACUGUGAAACAGCAAAGAUGGUAGUCUGCUCCUUCCUCUGGGAGCUCUGUGCCAGCAAGGUAUGGACCUGUUGCUUGCCCAAACACACCUGUAGUUGGUGGCUGGAGACCCCACAUUUCUCUAAUAUAUGUCAAGUUUACUGCAUGGUGCCUAGGUCUGGGAAAUGGGAAGUUGAUGAGACAUAACCCUGGUCCUCAAGAACUCUCUUUGUAGUGGGGGGAGCUAAGAUGUCCAUAAAGGACUCAAUGACAAGGUGAAAGAGAGGAGUAGCCUGAGAGCUGUAUUACCUAAGUUCAGAGAAGUUUGAGAAAAGAUAGAGUUGAUACUGGCUUUAAAUGAUUUGGGUAAAUGGAGAUGUGCAGCUUACAGAGAGUAGUAGAUGUAAAUGGUUAGGUGCUGGAAAGUAUAACUAUGUUUGGGGAAUGGUGUUAGUGGUAUGAUUGGUAUGGUUUAAUGUCUAUGAAUAAGAAUAGCAGAAGAUCAAAUUGUCAAAGUAAGUAUUACCAAGCUUAUGAGUUUGAAUUUUAGUGUGUGUGCUGGUGGUUUCUAAACUUUUGAUUGUGUCCCCUCAGUUAAAAUAUUACCCCUGCCCACAGAUGUAGGCAAUAUAAAAUGGGGGUUUUAAAAAGGAGAAAAAUAGAAAUACAUAUUAGUAAUUUCUUUCCCCACCUCAGUAGUUCCUCUUGCACAUAUCCAGUUUAGAAUCAUUGUCAGCUACUGGUGUUAUUGUUGGAGAUGUGUUUUAGCAAUAGGGAUAUGAAACAUCUUCAUGUUUUUCUCCAUAUGUAUAUGUAUGUACAGAAAAAUUACACAUUAUAUAUACACACAUAAUUUUAUUUUAGAAAAACAAAGCUAUUGGCAAUAUUCAUGGAAUAGUAUUGGAUAAAAGUUAUUUUCUUGUUUUAGUGAAAUAUUUUAGGUUUUUGAUAGAACUGGUUUCAUUCAUUACAGAAGUCAGUAUUGUAUAUGAAAGUUUUUUGAAAAUUCCAAAGUGCUGUGUAUAUUAGGUGUUUCUUUGAAGGGAUAGUUCAGGUGAAGAAUUUUUUUUUUUUUUUUUUUUUUUUGGAGAUCCAGUCUCGCUCUGUUGCCCAGGCUGGAGUGCAGUGGCGCGAACUCGGCUCACUGCAAGCUCUGCCUCCCGGGUUCACACCAUUCUCCUGCCUCAGCCUCCCUAGUAGCUGGGACUACAGGCGCCUGCCAUCACACCCGGCUAAUUUUUUUUUUUGUAUUUUUUAGUAGAGACGGGGUUUCACCAUGUUAGCCAGGAUGGUCUCAAUCUCCUGACCUCAUGGUGCAUCUGCCAUGGCCUCCCAAAAUGCUGAGAUUAAAGAUGUAAGCCACCGCGCCUGGCCCAUGUGAAGAAUAUUUUAAGAAGUUUUGGAUUUUCCUUUUAUUUCUCUCUAUAGUGCUUUGCACAGUUCUGUGUUUCAUAAUUAUGGAAAAUAUUGGCAAGAAUUUUAAUGAUUCUCUCAUUUCAAGUUUUCUUUGUUUUCUAGUUGCCAGUAAAUUUUAUCAUAUAGAAAUAAUUUUUAGAGGAGGAAAGCAUUUUAGAGUUUGUGUAGUAAUUAUUUGUGUGCUAUCUUGCCCUCUUCCUUGGCAAGUAGACUAUAAAAAACUGUAGGCUUAUAGAUAUUGUCUUAGUUUGGGCUGCUGUAACAAAUUAUCACAGACUGGGCAACAUCAACAACAGACUUUUGUCAUCAUUUUGGAGGCUGGUGGGGGCCUGCUUCCUGGUUUGCAGAUGGCUGUCUUCUCAUUGUAUCUUCAAAUGGUUGAGAGCAGAGAAAGAAGCAGCAAACUCUCAUGACCUUAUUACCUCUCAAAGGCCAAUGGAUAUAUUUGCUUGUUCUAUUAUUCAUGGUAGUACUUAGCAAAGUGUUUUCUAAGAGGCUGUCUAUAAAACUUACCAAGCAGGCCUCUUCAUUUUGCCCAUGAACGUCUAGCCUCAGAAAGGUUGAGCGGCCUGCAAGAACUCACAUUGCUCAUUAGUGAAAGACCUGGGUCUUUUGCUAUAUGUCUCUCGAAACUCAAGUUCAUUGCCUGUUCUACUAUAGUUUGUUGCCUCUCCUGCUUUCUCUGAUUUACCCUCAAGCAGGUGUUUCCAUUGCAUAUUUUAAAUACUUCAGCAGCUCCAGGGUACAGAUUGUGUUAUAUUCAACUUAGUGAUCUCUGAUACCCAGCACAAUGCCUUAUGGAGUAGAUGCUCAGGAUCUGAUGAAUUACCUUGUGAGAGCUGCAUGUUUGCAUACUCUUGAUUUGUUGAGAAAACUAAAGUAACUUGGGGUUGCACCUCAGUGUACUGUUUAUAAAAGCAAAGAUUAAACUGUAUACCUGAUAAUAUGUGUGAAGUGCUGUACAUGCAGAAUAUUUCUGAAAUCCCAAUUGCAAAUGUUUAUGAACUCGGAAAACUCCUGAAGAACUGUUGCAGUUGGCUGCAGUAGUUCAAGCUGUUAUUCACUGGACAGUUUUUCUCUGCAGUAUGUAAGAUGUGAAUUUUAUAUUUUGCUUCAAAAUUUAUGAUGCAGCAUAAACCAGGUUUAAAGUCUAGCUACCUUGCAAGGAGCAGCUUCCUUCUUCAUGGUUGAACUCUCCAGAGUAAUCCUUGGGUUGCUAUUUUUGUGGUCACCUUUGUGGAUUUUUUUCUCUUUCCUCAUUCAUGGAAAAGAUCAGACCCCCUAUACUUUUUAUAAUAAACUCUAAUUUUCCAGAUCAUUUAUCAUACUUAAGAAUUAUAAUUACCCAUUUUAAAAGCUUCAGCCUAGAUUGGCUAGAAAAUACUUAAUAUUUUUAUACAUUAUUUAUCCUUUUUUUUUUCACUGAGCUGUGUUGCUUUCAUUGACACCUGAAUGCACUGAAACACAGAUUUUAUCCCUAUGCCUACUUGUGAUGAGAAAGUAUCAGCAGAUUCAGUUGCUAGGAAACAGCUGAAUACUGAAAUAGUUUUUUUUUUUGGUGGGGAGGGGUACUUGUAAAUUCAGUUCUUUGACACGUCUACUCUCAUACAGCAAAAAUUUCUUCGGUCACUACAAAGAAAGAUGCAUCACCUGUUAGUUUUCCAAUUUAGAAAUUUUGCACAGGGGAGCUGGGCAUAUGUAAAUGUUACAGGGUUGAUAAAGUGCUGAGAGUGUAAUUUUUAACAGUGACUGGACAUUGUAAAGUAAUGAUUAUGUAUAUGCCUUUGAGUUUCAGUUUUCUCAAAAUUUUCUGAUUCAUCAUUAAUGAGAGAAAGAGCAAGAACAAGAGAGAAACAUAUGCAAACACAUACACAUGACACAUAGGAAUUUAAACCAAAGUAAAAUACUGUAUUAAUUAAACUAACUUUCUCAUAGUAAUAGGAUUGGCCACAUCCUAUAUUAAAUUACCCAGCUCUGGAUUUUUACCUGUGAUGCUUAAUAAUUAUGUGCCAGAGCAAGAAUAAAUGUUAAAAAGAAGUGUGUGGUUUAACUUUCUUUUAUAACUGAUUGCCAUUUAUUUUUGUCAUAGUAGUAUAACCUUUAAGUAACUUUUCCUGAGUAGCCACUAUGUGCCAGGCAAAAACAUGGGAGACAUAGGUAUGUUUAAGCUUUCAGGGUGCCUAGUAUGUGUGAGAGGUGGCAGCCAACAGAUUAAAUUGAGAACAUAUAUGAGAAAUUUAAUUGUGUCUGGUACACAGUAUAUGCUUAUUAAAAAAUUAGAAACCUGCCUUCAUCAUCAGUACCACCAUCAUCAUCAUCACCCAGCAAGCCAAUUCUUCAACUAAAAUCAGUUCAGAGUAAGCAGGGAGACAUAUAAACAGUCAUCAUAUGUGUGGUCAAUAAAAAGAGAAGUCUGUACCAGGUAAAGAGGCAGCACAGAAAAUAGAGUGAUGGACUUGUCUGGGGAUUGCAGAGAGAGCUUCAGAGACGUCAGGUCUGAGCUGGAUUUUGCAAGGCUCUCUCUUAGAUGUAAGCAUUCCCUUGACCUUGUCUUUUUUAGGGAGUAGGGAGUGGGGAGUAAGACCACUGCUUUUUUUUUCCUUCUUAAAUUUUUUAAGUUCUCUCAUUUCUUCCUUGUCCAUACCCUUGCUGAUAAUGAGGCUUGACAUCUAUCUUCCUGCCUGCUCCAUUCAGACAGAUGAGUACCGUCCAUGGUUUCUAAUUCUGUACCUUCAAUUUUCACUGCUUGUCUGUUUAAUUGCACAUAUACGUUUAGGAAUUUGUCAAGGAGUACAGAAUCCAUCUUCUGAUUUACAUGCAUUGAGAGUCUUGUGUCUCAGAAAUGAAAAUCUUAAUAAGGCUUUUCCAUCUUUAUCCGAGUGACAGAGAGAACCCUGUGAACUUAAGUAGGCAGUAUAUAUACUAAAAUUGGAGUGGUGCAGAAAAUGUUACCCAACAAGUUCUAGGAGAGUAAUGUGUAAGUUCAAAUAAAAAAUAAAAACAAAAAAUGAAAAUCGUCUGAGACUAGUUGAUUGGAAAUAACCAAGGAAUGAGAGAAUUGAGAAUAACAAGCUUGGUUUCCCUUAAAAUUUUAAAGGGGUACUAAGAGUAGAAGGAAAUGUUUUAUGAGACUCUUGCUGUUUUGUAUAAAAUCUUAUUUUUAAUAAUUUUAUAUUUUUCAUGCCUACAUUUUAAAAGAGAGACCUAACAUACAGUUAUGAGACUUCAGAAAUAUCAUGGAAAGUACUUAUGCUCUGGUUGCGGUUGUCCCUUGUGGCACUAUGAUUUUGUUCAUGUAUAAGAUUGUAUUUGUUGAGUUGCAAAACAGCCAGGUGAACAGUGUCAUUGAGUUUACUAAAUUGAGGUGUGAAUAAGGUAAUGAUCUAGAAAACAGAUAACUGAACCUGGAAAAAGAUAUAGAAGACAGAUUACUUGCUUAUAAAUUUGAAACAAAAGAAUGGUAAACAAGAUUGGUAACCCGAAUGUUAUCUUCUUUAACUGUGUCAUCAAAAACUCCACAGUUAUAACAUUGACUAUUAAAGGCUAAAAUAAUGGAAAGGAAAUGAAAUAAUGUUCAAUCUUUGAGGAAAAAAUGAAUAUACCUUUUUGGAUUUUGGCGGGGCAACUAUAAUCUCAAAGAAAGAGAAUAACAAUUUGCAUUUAUAAUCUUUUCUUCUAAGUAGCUUAAAGUUUUGUAAGUAUAUUUUCAUUAAUCCUUUGGACUAUAUUUGAAUUUUGUUCAAAAUAUUAAGAAGGAAAUAAUCUGUACUUCUUGUAGAUGGCUGAAAAAAUGACAUACUGAAAGUCACAGAUUUUUUUUUUCACUUAAAUGGCUUCAUUGUUUUAUGUUUCCAGUGUGGGUUUUUUUUUUGUGUGUGUGUGAAAGCAAGUUUAUUAGGAAAGUAAAGGAAUAAAGAAUGGCUACUUUAUAGGCUGAGCAGCCUCCACUGUUAUUUUUUAGCACUUUGCCUAAGGAAUUUAUUUAUCCUUCAAAUACGUAUCAUUUGCAUAUUGCGGGUUAGGCCUGAGGCGGUACACAGUGGCACACCCACAUGGGGUGAAGAGCAGGGAGAAAAAGAGAAUUUGAAACUGUGUAUUUUCUCCUUCAAUUUCAUGUGGCAUUAAAUCAUUCUUUUGAGGUCAAGAGCCUCUGAACUGAUUAGUUAAAGAAUUGGCUUGCUGGAUGAUGAUGGUGGUGGUAGUGGUGGUGAAGGCAGGUUUCUAAUUUUUUAAUAAGCACAUACUGUGUACCAGACACAAUUAGAUGUAUUAUAUGUGUUCUCAAUUUAACCCUGUUGGCAACGUUAUGAGAUGGUUAUUUGCAUGAAUUUUGCAGAGAGGGAAACUUGGGAAGGUUGGGUAACUUAUCCAAGGUCACAGAAUUCUAAGCCAAUGUACCUGUAUCUGUAAUUUUUAUGCUCGUGAUCUUUAAUGAUGUUACUCUCCCCCUUUGUGGGAAGCAGGCACAAAUAUUCCUUUUUUUUCCCCACUUUGGAUACGUGUUGGUGAGCAUAAAUGUGCCAAUCAUUGUGAUAUGGCUUCGAUGAGUGGAAGAACACCAGGGCUCUUGUCUCAUGCCCAAUUAGAUAAGAUGACAUGGGUGCAUGUGGAGUGGUUUUAAGGAGCGGAGAGUUUAAUAGGCAAGACAGAAGGGAGAA